GAUUCCCGCACGCUGCAGCCUCCCGGUCAGACGAAUUUCUCCCAAUCGGAUGAAGUUCACCCUGGGCCUGGGGUCGCGGGCGUGGAGAGUGUCCUGGGAGGGGGCAGCAGCGGCGGCGGCAGGCCCUGGAGCGGGCGGCAGCGCGCUCCGCUGCCGCGCACAGCGCGUCUCCAGCCCGCGGCUGGGCCGCCGCGGCUCUCGGCUCUCGGGCGCCCUCCCUCUAUGCCUCUCACGCGGCGGCGGCGGCGCCCAAGCUCUCCCGGACUGCGCCGGGCCCAGCCCCGGCCACCCCGGCCACCCCGGCGCCAGGCAGCUGGCCGGCCCGCUCGCUAUGGAGCAGACGUAUGGCGAGGUGAACCAGCUGGGCGGUGUGUUCGUCAACGGCCGCCCCCUGCCCAACGCCAUCCGCUUGCGCAUUGUGGAGCUGGCGCAGCUGGGCAUCCGACCCUGUGACAUCAGUCGGCAGCUCCGCGUAUCCCACGGCUGCGUGAGCAAGAUCCUGGCGCGCUACAACGAGACCGGCUCCAUUCUGCCCGGGGCCAUCGGGGGGAGCAAGCCCCGCGUCACCACUCCCAACGUGGUCAAGCACAUCCGGGACUACAAGCAAGGAGACCCUGGCAUCUUUGCCUGGGAGAUCCGCGACCGGCUGCUGGCCGACGGCGUCUGUGACAAGUACAAUGUGCCUUCGGUGAGCUCCAUCAGCCGCAUCCUGCGCAACAAGAUCGGCAGCCUGGCGCAGCCCGGACCGUACGAGGCAAGUAAGCAGCCGCCGUCGCAGCCUACGCUGCCCUACAACCACAUCUACCAGUACCCCUACCCCAGUCCCGUGUCGCCCACGGGCGCCAAGAUGGGCAGCCACCCCGGGGUCCCGGGCACGGCGGGCCACGUCAGCAUCCCGCGCUCAUGGCCCUCGGCACACUCGGUCAGCAACAUCCUGGGCAUCCGGACGUUUAUGGAGCAAACAGGGGCCCUGGCUGGGAGCGAAGGCACCGCUUACUCUCCCAAGAUGGAAGACUGGGCCGGCGUGAACCGCACGGCCUUCCCCGCCACCCCCGCAGUGAAUGGGCUAGAGAAACCUGCCUUAGAGGCAGACAUUAAAUACACUCAGUCGGCCUCCACCCUCUCUGCCGUGGGCGGCUUUCUCCCCGCCUGCGCCUACCCGGCCUCCAACCAGCACGGCGUGUACAGCGCCCCGGGCGGCGGCUACCUCGCCCCGGGCCCGCCGUGGCCGCCUGCGCAAGGUCCUCCUCUGGCGCCCCCCGGGGCCGGCGUAGCUGUGCAUGGCGGGGAACUCGCGGCAGCAAUGACCUUCAAGCAUCCCAGCCGAGAAGUGGCUGACAGGAAGCCUCCCAGCUCCGGCAGCAAGGCCCCGGACGCCCUCAGUAGCUUACACGGACUGCCCAUCCCGGCCUCGACCUCCUAGGGGCAGCUCUCCCCGGACCCGAGCCCGGAGGGAACGGCAGGCGGACCCGGGCGCACAGGUCUGCGCGGCGGCCCCGGCAAUCGGCACGGGCAGGAUCGGAGGACUCGCGGAGGAGGAAGCCAGUGCCGGCCCGCGGGGUGCACGCCCAGCCAGCCCCCAGGCCCAGCCCUGCCUCUGGCCGGACCCACCACACUUCCUUUAUUGGUCUGGGUUUUUAGGCUUCUCUGAACUUGGGUUUUAGACUGCCGUACCCUCCUCACAAUCCUUGCUCUGACGUGGCCUCCUUCGCUCUGCCAGCUUCAAAUUUCUUUUUUGUCACUCCCUUGUCCGUCUCCGUCUCGCCUCUCUCCCUGUUUCCUUCCCCCCUCUUUCUUUCUCACUCUCCCUCCCUUCCCUUUCUCUUUCCCUUCCUCCCUACCUUCCACCCCGGCUUUCCCCGACCUUCCAGGGCUCCCUCUGCCCUUCCACUCUCUUUUCCUUGCUCCGACCUCUGCUCCAGUCCCGCUUCUUCCCCCGUCUCCUCUUUCUAGUCCUCUAUAUGCUAUCAGCCCUUUUUCCUGGUCCAUCCCUGUCGUUCCUUCUCUCUCUGUCUCUGGUUCUACUGUCAAGGGCCCUAGUUCCCUUUGUUUUACUGCUUCCCCAACCCUCCCUCAGUCCCUGAGAGCCCUAGAGCCAUCUCGGUGACAGUCCCUUCUCUGGCACCUGGGACUUUGUAGCCUUCACUCCUCUGAGCCCACCAGCCCUAAUGGAGGGGGGCUCAAACCUAGGAAGUGGACAGAAAAGCCACAGCCUUUAUUUUGUAUUUUUUUUGUAAUAACAAACCCUAAAAAACCCUCCAUGAACUGUCCUCUCCCGUCGAUCCCCGCAGCAUAUUGUCUGGAAAUCUGUUUUCUUUCUCAGAGCCCAGUGGCCGCCGGGCUUCUCUUCCCUUCUGAGAUGAUGUCACCCCAAAGAAGACUGGGGUAGGAGUAGGGAGCACAGGGGUUGUUGGUGUUUUCAGUGCUUAGAAAACUGGGUUGUCCUGCAGGUGUCUCCUCCCACCCCUCCACUCGCAACACUUGCUAGGGAAUCCGACCAGUGGUAAACACAUCAGCACUUUUUGGUGUUCAGGGGUCAGCACAUUUGUUAAUUUAAACCACAGACUGCUUCCAGGUACAAAGGUUCAUUUGGACUUCUGGUUUGCAAGGGAUGAGGGUUAAAAAAAACAAAACAAAACAAACAACAACAACAACAAAAACAACCCAGAAAGUAUCUUCUAGAGCCAGCCGCAAGAGCUGUGAGCUGCUUCCAAGUUAGGCGAGCUGGUGGUGGUACCCUGGACAUAAUGCAAUUCUGUAGUCAGAGCAAUAUCCCUGGCGAGAGCCUGACAUCGCCUGUUAAAGGUGGCUGCCUCUGAAUAAAGGAAAGCGUCUGAAAGGUGUGUGGUGAGGUGAGCAAGUCUGUUUCUGAGCGCAGAGUGUUGAGUUCUUACUCCGUAGCUACCCUCUCCCCUGAGUUCCUAGGAUGAACACUAUCAAGGGAAAUUAUGCAGAAACCACCUUGAAAUGCAGUUAAUUCUGAAAAGAGUAAAAUGGGCAAAAGGCAAUGAGCCAGAAUGGAGGAUUUCUUCAGAACAUUUCUAGUAUUCUAAAAGCUAAAGAAGACAAUCCCAGGCUACCAAGUAAUCUAGGGGGUUUGCACUACAAAGGGGCUUCCGGCUAAUUGUUUUUUUUUCCUGCCUCUGUUUGACCUUCUAAAACUGAUGGAAGAGAUUUUUGAAUUGAAGUUGCUGUUUGUGAGUGGAGCUGCCUGCUUGGUGUGUGCACUGGUCCCACCUAGGGGACUAGUGGUAAACAGUUUUUGUUUCAACUCUUUUUGAUAGUAUCUGUUGAAGGUAUCAAUUAUAAAAAAGUACUUACUUUUUUCCUAGAGAGACUCUUCUUCUCAGAUUCAAAGUCUCUUGUCUUUUUUUUUUUUUUUUUUUAAAGUUUCACUUUGUAGACAGUGUUAGUGAUGGCUAGGGAUUUGAUUUAUUUUCUUUAGACCACAUAGCAAGGUAUGAAUUAGAGGGCUUGUGCUUGGAAACUGGGUGACACUAUCUCAUCAGAGAGGCAGGAUUGAGACUUGGACUUUGAGACUGAAGUCCUCAGCCUUCCAUGGCAGCAUAUCCUGUAGAAGAGCUUGUCAUACUGAUAAUAGGAAAAAAGUAUGACAGAGAAGCAUGUUCCCAAGUCCCCCAUCCUCUCAGCCUGUCUCCUUGUGCUUAGAUGAGCAUUGCAUGCUCAGUGGUGACAUCCUGGACAGAAUUUUCAUGCACCCAUUUGUGCUGCCUGGAGAAGGACUGGCUUGCUCAGGCCAGGAGGAAGACAUCACAUCCCUUUCUGAAGGAAUGAGAAGAAUCUAUAUGACAACUUCUACCUUUGAGUUGUCACCAUCCCCAUUUCCCUGCUAUGGCCCACUUCUGUGUUUGAGCUGAUCAGGGUUAUGGGGGAGAAGAGCUGGGAAAUGCGCCCCAGGGUGGAUGCAAAGCACCUGUGUUUUAAGUGCCACCUGCAAAGGGAGGCAUUUUUCAAAUCUGCCUCUUGUUCCCUGUAUCCUGUGGCUGGAGGCGGGUCUUUGAGUUCCCUGGCUCUGGGGCGAGCAUUCACUGAGGAUAGGCAGCCUUCGUCCCAGAGCCAGCAGGCUCUGACAUUUCAUGUGGGGUGUGGAGGGACAUACCCCCUCUCUCGCGGCUGGGGGUCACGGAACAUCUUAGUGAACUUGGCUUAAAUCUCUGCUCCACUGUAUGUGUCAGGGGACUGGGACCUCUUGGAACCUGUCUGUGAAAUGUAGCCUUCAAUGCAGUAACGCGCACGGUGACCUGGCCUGUAGGAAGACUGCCACUGGUGUGGCCUCACCUCUCUGGAGACAAUUUUGCUUAUCUGUUAACAAAAGUUAGAGGAAUCACUUGUAAGGUUGGUGGGAGACCCAGAAUUUAAAUAUUUUCCAAAAGAUCCCAUUGGAAUAUUGCACUUUUGCUCUUUGUUCGUAUGGAUCUGUGGAGGAACUGAGAGCUCAUAAUAAAAUUAUGCAGCACCACGUCAGGUAGAAUAAUUUGAGAAACAAUCACUCCCUAAACGCAGUUUGUCUUUGCCUUUCAUUUUUUUAAUUUAAGAAUAAGUUUUUUUUAGAAAAAUAUAGAGAUGUAACCCAAAGAAAAUAAAGACAUAAUCAGAUAGCCCUCUGAUUUUUUGAAAGAAUAGAAAUAAUAUAUGCGUAUCACUAAAAAACUCAAGCAGUACAGAAACAUUAAAAUGAAAAGUGGAAGUUCUUCCUGCUCUCAUUUUUGUUCUUAAAGGUGAAUGCUGUUAUAGUCUUUUGUGAAUCUUUCCAGGAAAAACAUGCAUGCGGGAAAAUAUGUUUCUGUCUAUGUGUUAUUUGAAAGUGCACACUAAUGAGUUGUGCUGUGCACACACAGACAUGAGCUGAAGAUCUGCUCUUUGCGUACCACCAGCUUCAGCUCCAAUGUACCCACUUUAUUCUCGUGAAUGGAUGUCUAUUACCGAGGAUUUAUUAAAAACAGGGUAUUUGUAAAGAGGGCCAGCUUCGUGCUUUAAAUGAAUAAAGACAGGAUUUUGUUGUGUUCAUUAUUGGAGGAAGUACUUGCAAUGGAUUGUAAUAACUUCCCUGCCAAAGGUAGCUGUUUUUUGGCAAGAAGUAAGGAAAACAAACCAAAGGAAAGGAGGAUUGAGGGGCAAGAGGCAUGAAGUUUUGCCCUUCUUGAAUAUGCCCCGAGUUGUUCUACAGAUCACUGAAGGGCAUUUGAAGGUGUGAGGGGAAGGCUUCCUCUCCUUUGGAGGGAGUCAGUCUCUCUGGGCCAGGAAAGAGACAUGGAGGCAGAGGGGUGCGGGAAAACCUUGUGUGAAGAAAUACUGGCUACAAAUAAAGUUUAGAUUUUCAA